CUUUUCCUGAGCCGCUUGGAUCUUUGUGGAAGCGGGUGGGCUGCAUAUAUACAGGACGGAUUCGUAUAGGCUUGCACCCUGGUUCCGAAUUUUGCAAAUAUUCGCAGUCUGGGUCACUGUCAUCCGGACUGGGAAUCCCCAAGACCCGUUAAGGGAGGAUAGAAGGAGCUGGACCCUAGCUGCCCCAGUGGGCAAGGACACUUGAAGAUCAAAUCUGUUCCGGCCUGGCAGCCUCUCCCCAGCUGGGCAGGGGCCCCAGGCACCGUGAUGUGGAGUCAAGCCGCCUAUACCUCCCUUGGCUGCCCCAGGGCUGCUAGGAUCCAGCAAUGCCUGUGAGAAAACCUCCUUCACCUUCCUCAGGCAGGAGCUGCCUGUGCGCCUGGCCAACAUCAUGAAAGAGAUCAACCUGCUUCCCGACCGAGUGCUGAGCACACCCUCCGUGCAGCUGGUGCAGAGCUGGUAUGUCCAGAGCCUCCUGGACAUCAUGGAGUUCCUGGACAAGGAUCCCGAGGACCAUCGCACCCUGAGCCAGUUCACUGACGCCCUGGUCACCAUCCGGAACCGGCACAACGACGUGGUGCCCACCAUGGCACAAGGCGUGCUUGAGUACAAGGACACCUACGGCGAUGACCCCGUCUCCAACCAGAACAUCCAGUACUUCCUGGACCGCUUCUACCUCAGCCGCAUCUCCAUCCGCAUGCUCAUCAACCAGCACACCCUCAUCUUUGAUGGCAGCACCAACCCAGCCCAUCCCAAACACAUCGGCAGCAUCGACCCCAACUGCAACGUCUCUGAGGUGGUCAAAGAUGCCUACGACAUGGCUAAGCUCCUGUGUGACAAGUAUUACAUGGCCUCACCUGACCUGGAGAUCCAGGAGAUCAAUGCAGCCAACUCCAAACAGCCGAUUCACAUGGUCUACGUCCCCUCCCACCUCUACCACAUGCUCUUUGAGCUCUUCAAGAAUGCCAUGAGGGCGACUGUGGAAAGCCAUGAGUCCAGCCUCAUUCUCCCACCCAUCAAGGUCAUGGUGGCCUUGGGUGAGGAAGAUCUGUCCAUCAAGAUGAGUGACCGAGGUGGGGGUGUUCCCUUGAGGAAGAUUGAGCGACUCUUCAGCUACAUGUACUCCACAGCACCCACCCCCCAGCCUGGCACCGGGGGAACGCCGCUGGCUGGCUUUGGUUAUGGGCUCCCCAUUUCCCGCCUCUACGCCAAGUACUUCCAGGGAGACCUGCAGCUCUUCUCCAUGGAAGGCUUUGGGACCGAUGCUGUCAUCUAUCUCAAGGCCCUGUCCACGGACUCGGUGGAGCGCCUGCCUGUCUACAACAAGUCAGCCUGGCGCCACUACCAGACCAUCCAGGAGGCCGGCGACUGGUGUGUGCCCAGCACGGAGCCCAAGAACACGUCCACGUACCGCGUCAGCUAAGGGCCGCCGUGCAUCUGCACCUGAGAGGACGGACUGCCGCCUCUGGGUCCCCCCACCGUGGUGCCCCUCACCAUCCUCCUGGGGGAGCAGGGGGUGGGUUCUCCCUGAUGACCAGGUUCUGUCUCUAUGGAAGUCACUGCGGUGAUAGGUCUGUGAUGGUCCCUAAGUGCCAGUCCAUCUCUGUGGAGACCCCUCGGUGGCCUCCCUAUCUCUGUGGGCGAUGCCUGAGGGUUAGGGAUGUCUCCACCCUGAUGGGGUGUCCCAGAGACAUUUUCCCAUGGCAGUCCUCCUCUCUGAGACCAGGGCUGUCACUUUUCUGCCAGGGGUACUGGGUCCCCCUCAGCACCCUCCACAGCACAGGCCUUCCAAGUGGAUGUCCCGUUGCCUUAUUCCCCCAGCCCACAAAGGCACCCUGGCCUUGGCCUGCUGAAGUGUUAGGAAGAGGGUGGGUGCCCUCCAGACCUGGGGACUGAGUGGGGAAAGGAGUUACACCCGUGAGUGGGGAAUGAGGCUGGUCCUGCAGCCUCUCCCUCCGCUCAGGGCUUGAAGGUCGGUGGCGGAGGGGGUGGCUCUCACAGGGCCCAACUCUAAAGUGGAAGAACCUUGUUAGACCGAGAGCUUGCCAUCCAGCCAAGCUGCUCGAGGCCCUGCAGUGGCCUUGGCAAUGUCUGUGCCACCUCCUGAGCCCUCCCAGCAUGUCCUCACAUGCUCAUGCCCACCCGCUCCUCCACAAGCCUAGUCCAUCCUGCCUGAGCUCCAGCCCCCAGCCCCCACUGUGCCCAGACAUGUGUGCUCAGGGUGGCUUUCUCCCUAGGACCUUCUGUGUAUAUAGUUAGUUUUAUAACCCUGAAUGCCCCCACCCUUCCCCUAAGCACACAGGGGUUAAAGCUGUGUGUCCCUCCCAGUGGCUGUGGCAGUGACAGUGACACCCACACCCACAGUAAAGAGGAGACUGAAUGAGACUGGCCUGGCUGCAUCCCUGGGGGAGGGGACCCACACGUGCGCACGUACACACGCACACUGCGGUGCCCUGUGACCACCACAUGACGCACCGGGGACGUCCGGCCCAGCUCAGGACUGUGAGUAAAACACUGGGCAAAGCCAUCUGUUCAGAACGCCGGAUGGCCCAGCACCUGGUGACAGACCUGUUGUCCCACCAUACUCAGGGCCCAGCAGAGUCCGGCCAACCCAACAACUGGAGCAGACAGAAAUUCUGGUCACUGGCACAUCAUAAGGAUUUAUUGAAAUAAAUUGAGAACUGCCUCCCCUUCACAUGCAGGUGGGCACCCACUAUAGCUACUGAUGGCUUUAAGGAUGUGGGUGCCUUCCAACCUCCCAUGGCCCUGCCACCAGGCCCAGAUGGUGCCAGUGUCCUCAUAUCUGUUUCCCUCCGAAGCCCCUCUCCCAGCACAGAUAGCAGAGGGGGGAUAAGGGCUGAGUCCCAGGUACAGGGUGCUGGCCGUAAGCCACAGCCCCUGGGCAGGAAUGAGGGAGCCAGCAUGCAUUGGUGCCAUCUGCCGCUCUGUCUGGGCAGAUGGGAGGAGCUGGAGGGGUUUCCAAGCGGGAGCCCCCAGGCCUCAUCGGUAACUCUGACCAGUGUCCUGGAAGCGGGACUAGCUGCUGACCAGCGCCACACAUGAACACUUCCUCCAAGGACAUUUCCUAAAAAGGACACAUGCUGUCCCCAGGCUGCUGGUAAACUCCACCCCCAUCCAGGGAGCUGGCCCCAGCCCUCAGUGUGGCCCAGGGAAGCAGAGCUUGCACCGCCUGCCAGUUCUGAGCCCACUGAUUCCCUGACAAUGCCUGGGGCAGAUGGGGGAGGGCUGAUGAACCUUUCCAAUCUCGUAGCUGCCGGGGACCCCCAGGUUUUGCCUCUCUGCCUGGCUGGGGUGAGGGCUGACCAGGUCAGCAGCUCCUAGGCCUUGGCUGGUGGAAGUGGUGUCCUCUGUCCCUAUCAGUUCCUGUUUGCUCAGCUCCCAAAGAGGACUUAGGUGCCCUCUGAGGAAGCAGCAGGAAGUGAAGGGAGUCCUGGCUUGGAGAAUGGGUCAAAGACCA